ACUCCUGACCAGGCGCAGGACGCGGGGAGCAGCAGGCAGAGCAGCGGCCCGAGGCGGCCGGGGACCGGCCCGCGGGCUCCAUGGGCCGCGGCUACGCCGCCCGCGAGGGCUGGAAGGCACUAGAAGCGCCGCCGGGGCUGCCCAGAGGCCGGGUCCCCGCUCCACUUUGCGCAAACUUGUUUUUCUGAGGUCAGCGCUGCGAGCUGGCUACAUCGUCCUCUUAAGGUGGCCUGGGGAAGUUGCGGCCGACCUCCCCUCGCCUCCGGACUCCGGCCGCGCGGCUACUCCCGCUUCCCACUGGCGAGAGGCUGGAGGCGGCGAAGGAGUCGGGGAGUGGAGGCGCGGGGGUGGGGGGGUGUCUGCCUUUUAACCCUCCCCAAGAGGUCGUGCCUCUGAGCCCCAAAGCUGAAGGCCCCUCUUGGGGGUGGGUGCGGGCCGGAGGGGACCGAUCCUUUCAGAGCCGUGCCGAGGUGAAGGAAAAGCUGGAGUGGACUUUCUGUUCCGGGAGAACAUCCAAGAUGUGCUAUCUGCGCUGCCCAAUCCUGAUGACUACUUCCUCCUGCGCUGGCUCCAAGGAAAAGGGCCCCAAGGCCCACCAAGGGGCAUGCCCAGGGAAUCAAGGAGCCUGUGUCCAGUGUUCCUGGGUCUCCGGAUAUCUCAGCCAUUGUGGCUCCCCAGGUCAAGAACAAGGCCCUCUGGCUCGGAGCUUUGACCUGCAGAAAUCAGAGGACAUGCUGAGGAAGCAUAUGGAGUUCCGGAAGCAACAAGACCUGGCCAACAUCCUUGCCUGGCAGCCCCCAGAGGUGGUCAGGCUGUACAACGCUAACGGCAUAUGCGGCCACGACGGUGAGGGCAGCCCUGUCUGGUACCACAUUGUGGGAAGCCUGGACCCCAAAGGCCUCUUGCUCUCAGCCUCCAAACAGGAGUUGCUCAGGGACAGCUUCCGGAGCUGCGAGCUGCUCCUGCGGGAGUGUGAGCUGCAGAGUCAGAAGGUGUGUGGGUGCCACCCUGGGCAGCUGCAGCCGGACACAGCACCCUCACCCCCUGAGCCUCACACCCAGAAUCUGCCUUCCUGGGCUCCUGGGCUCCUCGGCUCCUCCUGGUACUGUGGAGUGAAUGCAGGUUCAGAGAGGCCAAGGACCCACCCAAGGCCACACAGUAUGUGGCUGAACUGGGAAUCAUUUCUCCCCCAAUUGGCCCCAAAGCCCACUCAAUCCACUGGGCCACACUGCCCUCUGCAGCCUCAUUGGACGAGAGGGACAGGGAUUUCAGCCCCACUGGACCGAAGAGGGAACUGCAACACAGCGAUUUGGCCUCCCAUGGACAGACACAAAGAGCUGGGGAAGAGGGUGGAGAAAAUCAUAGCUAUUUUUGGUCUCGAAGGGCUGGGCCUGAGGGAUCUGUGGAAGCCAGGAAUAGAGCUUCUCCAGGAGUUUUUCUCAGCACUUGAAGCAAAUUACCCUGAGAUCUUGAAGAGUUUAAUUGUUGUGAGAGCCCCCAAGCUAUUCGCCGUAGCCUUCAACCUGGUCAAGUCUUACAUGAGUGAAGAGACACGCAGGAAGGUGGUGAUUCUCGGAGACAACUGGAAGCAGGAGCUGACAAAAUUCAUCAGCCCCGACCAGCUGCCCGUGGAGUUUGGGGGGACCAUGACUGACCCCGAUGGCAACCCCAAGUGCCUGACCAAGAUCAACUACGGGGGUGAGGUGCCCAAGAGCUACUACCUGUGCAAGCAGGUGAGGCUGCAGUAUGAGCACACGAGGUCCGUGGGCCGCGGCUCCUCCCUGCAGGUGGAGAACGAGAUCCUGUUCCCGGGCUGUGUGCUCAGAUGUCCUGAGGUUUUACAACACCUACAGCCUGGUUCAUUCUAAACGCAUCAGCUACACCGUGGAGGUACUGCUCCCAGACCAAACCUUCAUGGAGAAGAUGGAGAAAUUCUAGGUGAACCUCAUGGUCCCCACACCCUCCUCUUUGAUCUCUGAAUCCACAAUGAGUUCACAGCCUUCCCUGGCCAGACCCUGUUCAACCUCUCAGGAACAGGGAUUCUACAACAGCAGGUCACAGCCUAUGCAUCACAGCUGGCCCACUCCUCAGGAACGGCUGGGACAGUGUCCUAGUGGUGGCCCGAUGGUCACAGCAAAGCAACACAGACACUCCAUCCCCACUAUGACCUGCUGUGACCUCAAGCUCAGCAAAAACCCCAGGCUUUUUUCUAUCAACCAAUACCAAGAAAUAAGUUACUCUUCUAAAAUAUAGUAUUAGGCCAGGCAUGGUGGCUCAUACCUGUAAUCCCAGCACUUUGGGAAGCCAAGGCGGGCAGAUCAUUUGAGGUCAGGAGUUCGAGACCAGCCUGGCCAACAUGGUGAAACCCUCAUCUCAACUAAAAAUACAAAAAUUAGCCAGGUGUGAUGGUGCCUGCUUGUAAUUCCAGCUACUUGGGAGGCUGAGGCAGGAGAGUCGCCUGAACUUGGUAGGCAGAGGUUGCAGUGAGCCGAAAUCAUGCCACUGCACUCCAGUCUGGGUGACAGAGUGAGACUCUGUCUCAAAAAAAUAAAAUAAAAUAGUAUUAAUAGGAAAUUUGAAAUAUAGUAUAGCUGACAGAUCAGGAAAUAAUUACCAUUGAAAAGAUAGUUUAUUACUCACAGUUCCCAAGAGGAGGGGCCGCUGUGCCAUAGGGGGAAGAGGAGGGGUCCCCAGGGAGGCAUCAGGGCCGAACAUGACGCACAUGAGACAGAAAAACUCUGGACAAAGCAACUUUACUUUUAUGAUGGUUUCUGCAGGAAGGAACUGGUGAGGCAGGGUAAGCAGGCUUGAGAUUUGCUAGUUUGAAUAAUUUCAGCAGGCUCCGUGGAAUAAGGGCUGUCACUAGCUGUCUGGUAUCUUGCCCUGGGGUGAUUACAGCAGGUGGAUAGUGGCCUGGAGUGUGAGAAUCUGAUAAAGGAGGUAGUUGGAAUAUGGUUUAUAUCAGUUGGUUUGCAUUCGAAAAGUGCAUUUGUGGGCAAGUUGCUGUAUCUCUAGGAGAGGCAGGCCCUCCAGGAUUAGCAAAACCUCAGAUGUUAAAGCAUGCAGAAAAUAAAAGACAUGGUUCAAAUAGUUCCCUAACAAGCAGUUGUGCAAUGCUGCUCUGAAUGGAAAUCCAACCUCACAGUUUCCCAUCUAGAAAGAAUUUUAAACUCUCUAUUCUGUCUUCCACAUACACGUUCCCUCCCACUGUUAUAGCAUCUGAGAAUCUGCUUGAGCUCUGGAUCUUCAUCCAAUCUCCUGAUUAAGAUUUCAAACUGGCCAGGUGCAGUGGCUCACACCUGUAAUCCCAGCACUUUGGGAGGCUGAGGCAUGUGGAUUGCUCGAGGCCAGGAGUUUGAGACCAGCCUGGACAACAUGGCGAAACCCCGUCUCUACGAAACAUACACAAAUUAGUUGGGUGUGGUGGCGGCGAGUGCCUGCAGUCCCAGCUACUUGGGAGGCUGAGGUGGGAGAAUCUGUGGAACCCAGGAGGCGGAGGUUGCAGUGAGUUGAGAUUGCACCACUGCACUCCAGCCUGGGAAACAGAGCAAGACCCUGUCUUAAAAAAAAAAAAUUCAGACUGAGCCUCACAGUGGGACACUAGGUCGGUGUCAGCCCACAGUCCUACUAGAGUGCUGUCCUGCGAUCAGGCCUCUUUGGGUCUGGCUAUGCUGUCAGCUGAGAUUCUGCCCAGGAUCCUGUCACUCACAUGUUGUCCCAGCUUGUUCUCAAUGUGGCAGCCCCAAAUGACAGCCAAAGUUCUUCCCUAAUUGCCUACUUUACAGGAAUCCUGUCCAAAAAUGGAAACACGGGCAUUCAGCAGCCCUUGCUCUCCCUCAGCCCCUCCCCUGACAGCCACUGAUCUGUUCUUCAUCCCUACACUUUUGAUUUUUUCCAGAGUGUCAUAUAAAUGGAAUCGUGCAAUAUUUAGCCUUUUGAUUCUGGCUUUCUUUAGUCAGCAUAAUGCCUCUGAGAUUCAUUCACUUUGUUGCAUGUGUUAAUAUUUAGUUGCUUUUCGUUGCUGAGUAAUAUACCACUGUAUGGAUGGACCACACUGUGUUUAUCCCUUCCCCUGUUAAAGGCUGGUUGAGUCGCUUCCAGUUUGGGGGCGAUUAUGAAUAAAGCUGUUGUAAGCA